GGGACUGUGGCUGUGGCCCCGGGAGAGCCGGGUGGGGCCUCGGGAUGCAGCCGCCGGUGCCCGGGCCCCUGGGCCUGCUGGACCCCGCAGAAGGGCUUUCGAGGAGGAAGAAGACGUCGCUCUGGUUUGUGGGGUCUCUGCUGCUGGUGUCCGUCCUCAUAGUCACCGUCGGGCUGGCUGCCACCACCAGGACGGAGAAUGUGACCGUUGGGGGCUACUACCCAGGGAUCAUUCUCGGCUUUGGAUCUUUCUUAGGAAUUAUUGGCAUCAACUUGGUGGAGAAUAGAAGGCAAAUGCUGGUGGCAGCGAUCGUGUUUAUCAGUUUUGGCGUGGUGGCCGCCUUCUGCUGCGCCAUCGUGGACGGCGUAUUUGCAGCACAGCACAUUGAACCGAGGCCCCUCACCACGGGAAGAUGCCAGUUUUACUCCAGUGGGGUGGGGUACUUGUACGAUGUCUACCAGACAGAGGUCACCUGUCACUCCCUGGACGGCAAGUGCCAGCUGAAGGUGAGAAGCAACACCUGUUACUGCUGUGACCUCUAUGCCUGCGGGAGCGCAGAGCCCUCGCCCGCCUACUAUGAGUUCAUCGGCGUCAGCGGCUGCCAGGACGUGCUGCACCUGUACCGCCUGCUCUGGGCCUCUGCAGUUCUGAACGUCCUGGGCCUGUUCCUGGGCAUCAUCACCGCCGCCGUCCUGGGGGCCUUCAAGGACAUGGUGCCUCUGUCCCAGCUGGCCUAUGGCCCAGCCGUCCCACCACAGACCCUCUACAACCCCGCCCAGCAGAUCCUGGCCUACGCAGGCUUCCGCCUGACGCCCGAGCCCGUCCCGACCUGCUCGUCCUACCCUCUGCCCCUUCAGCCCUGCAGCCGCUUCCCAGUUGCGCCCUCCUCUGCCCUGGCUUCGUCUGAGGACCUGCAGCCCCCUUCUCCAAGCAGCUCUGGCUCUGGGCUUCCCGGCCAGGCUCCACCGUGCUACGCACCCACCUACUUUCCCCCGGGGGAGAAGCCACCCCCCUACGCACCCUGAUAGAGGCGUGGAGUAAAAGAUAACUUGUUUGUUUUUUUUUUUAAAAAAAAGGCAGCCUCUAGAAAUCCCGCUUCUGUGGCCAACCUCCUAGAGAACCCGGGAGAAUGUUCCAGAAGUCUGUCCCCUCCUUUCCUCCCUGGGCACACUGGUGAGGGAGGCUGGAACCAGGCAGGGAGUGGGGCCCUCCAGACCCAGGCUGGUGACACCUUGGCUUGGGCUCUGCUCACAUCAAAUGGCGCUGAAAGUUCCCACCCGGCCUCCUCCUCUGAGAGCAAUUGUUCUGGUGUUUUCACAUCCCUUAAUUAAUUAGCUAUUAUUAUGAUUUUGCAAAGACAGUGCAGCCCCGGCCUCCCUGCCUGUGUGUUCUUGUUUGUGGACAUGUGUUGUGCGUUACACGUUCGUGUGUGCAUCUGUGUCCUGGAGAAGCGCAGGGCAGAAGCCACCCGCCCCUCGUGCUGUGCUCCUGACGUAUGCCAGGAAGGGAAGGACGCUUCGGCUCCAACGCCCAGCGCUGUGUCUAACCGCCUGUGAGUUGUUAGAAUCCAGGGGCCCGGUUGUCUUUCCCAGCCCCGGAUGCAAAUCUGCCUGGGCCACUGGCACGAGGGUCUUCCCCUGAGCUGUCUCCCAGCUACGGCGCCUGGGCUUCCGCUGUCCUUCCGCGGCUUCUCCCUCACCGCACCUUGUCUCAGGACCCCUGGCCGCUGGGAUGGUGGGGGACGGUGUUUCGGGGUCCUUUGGCUCAGGGUCUGGGGCCGCAGCACUCCCUGUGGAAACCAGCUUAGCUCCCCGCGGGCCCAGCAUGCACCUGCCGGGCACACCUGGGGAGACGGGUGAGCACGCCUGGGAAGCAGCAGGUCCCGGGUGGGUCACAGGCCCCGGGUGGGUCACAGGACAGGUCUCAGGUGGGUCACAGGUCCUGAGUGGGUCACAGGUCCCGGGUGGGUCACAGGCAUCCCGGGUGGGUCACAGGUCCCGAGUGGGUCACAGGCCCCGGGUGAGUCACAGGCCCCGGGUGAGUCACGGGUCCCGGGUGGGUCACGGGUCCCGGGUGGGUCACGGGCCCCGGGUGGGUCACGGGUCCCGGGUGGGUCACGGGUCCCGAGUGGGUCACGGGUCCCGGGUGGGUCACAGGCGCCCCAGUGACAGGAGUUCAGGAUGCGCCACCCCAAAGUAGCCGAAGUCUCUUGAAAAGUGUUGGAUGUGGGGAGAGGCUUUCUCUGAACUCCUGAAGUCAGAUCCUCAGGGAACCAGGGACUCCCAGGGCGGGAGGGCGGGCGAGAGGUGAUCCCAUUGCUCCCCAGACGUGCCACAAGACACCAAGUCGCCGUCUCUGCUCUGUGGGCCGCUCACGGUUCCCCAGUCACUCCCUCUCCCCUCGGAAGCUGGCGCCUCCAGGCCUCACCGCUCUCAGGGCCUCACGUCCCUCCCUGCAAAGCCCCCCGUGCCUACGAUAAACAAGUACCGCUCUUCUCCCGUGUGGGUCUGAGGUCUCCAGCUUACUUCACGGAACAGUGCCCACCUGGGAGGUGGAGCGGGGACUUUCUCCCCUGCCCAGUCCUGGAUCUGGGAGAAAAAAGAUAAGGUGGAGGGGAGCCACACUCGUGCAGACACAGCCUCCUGCCCCCUCUGCUGCCCGGGAGCCUCCCUCUGUCCGAUGGAGGGUCUCACACAGCCUCUGCCCCCUCCGCUGCCCGGGAGCCUCCCUCUGCCCGACGGAGGGUCUCAUCCUGUGUCCAGCGCUCCUGGGCAGAAGGCCCACAGCGCACAUCCACACAUGAACGGUGGCUGGCUGGGCCCAGGGGCCCUAACGGGCCUCUGAAAGGCCUGCAGCCAGCUCUGGUCUGUGAACCCGCCACUGCUUGUCAUUUUUAUCUUAUAAAAUCCAGCCUCACAAGCUUGCUGUCCAGGAGAAUGUGGUCUUGGCCUCUCAGGGCUGACUGGCCUUGAACCAGUCCGGGAGGUCGGGCACGAGCCGGAGGUGCGGCGUCCUGUCUGGAAAUCACCGCCCAGUUCCUCCAGGGCUGUGGGUGCCUGGCUCCGAGUAAGAAGCUGAACAAGCAGCAGAGACCAAGAGGUUUCUGGAGCGCCGGGAGAUGCACUCACGAGCGCCUGUGGGGGAAGAAAAGUGUGCCACGGAUUUCCCGAGUCCCCAGGGCUCUCACUUUACCUCAGGGAAGGCUCUAUGGGCGCCGAUGGUGCCGUGGUCUUGUGUGGGCGGUUCCUGGGCACCCUGGAGCUCGGGCUGUGCCCCCGAAGCUGCCUGGUGCAGGCACCAGCACCUCUUGGUGUCCUAGGGGUGCGAACAGCAGAGAAGCUGAACUGCAGGUCUGGGCAGGGAGUCUAUGCCCCCUGGAGCUCUGGCCAGCAAAGUCACAGGAAUAACCCUCCUUCCCCUCAUGUCAGCCCUCGGUCGCAGGGUGCGGUGUGGGGGCAUCAGAGUGCUUCCCCGAGGCUGCACUCACCAGCUUCCCCCAAACACAACAUCGAUCUUUCCCGACUUUUAAUCUUGUCUAGAGUCAAAAGCUGUUCAAAAAUAUUCAACUCCAAGGUCAACAGUUUUGUUCUUGCCACAAAAAUGUCCUUAUCCUUUAUCCCAGCCACAAAGAAUGUGAACAAUUUGACUCAAGGUUCGUGGUGGCUGGAGGGUCCCCCAGGUCCCAGGGCAGCUCCCACCUGGCGCAGGGCUCCGGCCAAUGCCUGGCCUGCAGUGUGGGCGGCGGCUGCUCUCGAGGUGCACCUGUCUCAUGUGGACGGAUCCUGUCUGGGGCCACCAAGCUCUGCCAGCCUGAGUCACGGUCUGAUGAACCCCCUCUCUGGGCUCCGCUGGGGCCUUCUGAUCCCAGCCUCCUCUGCAGGGAUGGGCUCCCAAUCCCGCCCUCACUUGGUUCCCAUGCACAGCCGAGGUCAGUGAGACCCUGGAGGCCGCGGGAGAUGGGGUGGAGGGGAUGGUGGGGCAGGGGGUGCUGGGGGGUUUGGGGGUGCUGUGGCCCCGGGGCAGGGGGUGCUGGGGGGUUUGGGGUGCUGUGGCCCCACCUGCACUCCCUGCCUCACUGGGACAGCACAGGAGACAGGCUUCUCCUGCAGCUCAGAGGUGGGGGCCUAGUGUAGCUGCAGGUUGUGACUGAGGAGGGCAGGGUCAGAGCAUUGCCCUGGGCAGGGGUCCGUUGAGACUGGCCCCACCUUAUUAGCUUGGGACCUUGGGUUACAGGGAGUCUCCUCCUGCCUCAGUUUCUACAUUUCACACAGCAGCACUGCUCACAAGAGCUCCCAAGCAGAGGCAACUACUGAGUGGGGGAGGGACACAGUCCGUCCACAUGGGGCCAACGGCCACAAAGAGAGGAAGGGACAUGGGUGACGGUCCGUCCACGUGGGGUCACCGGCCACGGAGAGAGGAAGGGACAUGGGUGACGGUCCGUCCACGUGGGGUCACCGGCCACGGAGAGAGGAAGGGACAUGGGUGACGGUCCGUCCACAUGGGGUCACCGGCCACGGAGAGAGGAAGGGACAUGGGUGAUAUGGUUUUGCUGUGUCCCCACCCAAAUCUCAACUUGAAUUGUAUUUCCCAGAAUUCCUGCGCGUUGUGGGAGGGACCCAGCGGGAGGUAAUUGAAUCAUGGUGGCUGGUCUUUCCCGUGCUAUUCUCGUGAUAGUGAGUAAGUCUCACGAGAUCUGACUGGUUGAUCAGGAUUUCCGCUUUUGCUUCUUCCUCAUUUUCUCUUGCUCCUGCCGUGUAAGAAGUGCCUUUUGCCUCCCACCGUGAUUCUGAGGCCUCCCCAACCAUGUGCAAUUGUAAGUCCCGUUAAACCUCUUUUUUUCCCAGUCUCGGGUAUGUCCUUAUUAGCAGUGUGAAAACAGAAUACUACAGUGGUCCAUCCACACGCGGGUCUCACCCAGCCACAGAGAGGGAGAGGACGUGGCCCAUCCACACGCGGGUCACCCGGCCACGGAGAGGAAGGAAGCUCUAACGGGUGCUGAGGCUGUAACACACAGUGCUCAGGGAAGGACACCAGACAUGAAGACUGUGUUCUGUUUAUAUGCAGUGUCCAGAGAAGGCGUGUCCACAGACAGAAGCCGACUGGGAAAGGAGGUGCAGUCACUGCUCAGGGACACGGGUUCUUUUCGGGGAGGCAAGCGUGUUCGCAGCGUGUUCUGUAUGGGGAGAGAUGCAGUCACUGCUCAGGGACACGGGUUCUUUUCGGGGAGGCAAGCGUGUUUGCAGCGUGUUCUGGAUGGGGAGAGGUGCAGUUACUGGUCAGGGACACGAGUUCUUUUCGGGGAGGCAAGCGUGUUUGCAGCGUGUUCUGGAUGGGGAGAGGUGCAGUCACUGGUCAGGGAUACGAGUUCUUUUCGGGGAGGCAAGUGUGUUCUAAGCGUGUUCUGGAUGGGGAGAGGUGCAGUCACUGGUCAGGGACACGAGUUCUUGUGGGAAGAGGAGUGUCCGGGAGCCAGAUGGCAGUGAUGGGUGGACGGCCCCGUGGAUGGACUGACCACCGACCCAUGCUCUGCACUCAUGAGGCGUGGCUAUUGCUGUGUGAAUCACAUCUCCAUGGAAACGGGAGUGGGAGAAACGGGCCCCAAGGAUGUUGUGAAGAUGGCCUUAUGGGGCUGCACUGGUGACUUGGACAGUGCUGGCCACCGGCCCUGCUCAGUGAACAAGAGCCAUGGUCAUCACCCUCGCCACACAGAGCAGCUCCUCCUGCAGACUUGGGGACCCCGUGGCCACCAGACCCCGCGGUGGGAGCAGAGAUGCCUCCGAAACUCUGGAGACCCACAGAGGCAGAAGAGGAUUCCACGAGGCCGGGGCCCGUCAGCAGAUCCUCAGACGGCGACACGCGCCACUUCCUUUUCUGUUUCCUAGACCUUUUAACUGAUGGAAUUCAGUAAGCAGAAAACGUGCUUGAAACAAGGGCACCAUGGAGCGGACCCUCCCCCUCUCCCCUCGUGGAGUCCUUGACCCUGGGGCAGGUGACCCUUCUUGCUUUGCAGGCAGGGGCUGUGGCUGGAGCUUCUCCUACAAAUGGGCUGUGCUGGGAUUAGCCCGGCUGUACAUUUGCUUUAUGCUUCCGUUGGCAUUUAAAAAUCUGAUGUUCAUA